AGUGCACGGGGCCUGGGUGGGGGGUGCGGGUGUGGGUGGGGACCUGCGGCCUUCGAGUCCGCGGCCUUCGAGUCCUGGGGCGGCGGCGGCGGCUGCAGGCACGGGCACGGGCACGGGGCGGGGUGCUUAGGGUGCAGGAGGCGCGCGCCUAGCGGCGGAGUGUGGCGUGAGGCCGGGCCCGCGCCGCCAUGAACCUAGAGCGGCUGCGGAAGCGCGUCCGGCAGUACCUCGACCAGCAACAGUAUCAAAGUGCUCUAUUUUGGGCAGAUAAAGUAGCUUCACUCUCUCGUGAAGAACCCCAGGACAUCUAUUGGUUGGCUCAGUGUCUUUACCUGACAGCACAAUAUCACAGAGCCGCCCAUGCACUUCGGUCACGAAAACUGGACAAAUUGUAUGAAGCAUGUCGUUACCUUGCAGCUAGGUGCCAUUAUGCUGCAAAAGAGCACCAGCAGGCCCUUGAUGUUCUUGACAUGGAAGAGCCCAUCAAUAAAAGAUUAUUUGAAAAAUACUUGAAGGACGAAAGUGGCUUCAAAGAUCCUUCCAGCGACUGGGAAAUGUCACAGUCUUCAAUAAAGAGUUCUAUCUGUCUUCUACGCGGGAAAAUCUAUGAUGCUCUAGAUAACCGAACCCUGGCUACCUACAGCUACAAAGAAGCUUUGAAGCUUGAUGUCUACUGUUUUGAAGCGUUCGAUCUUUUAACAUCACAUCACAUGCUGACAGCACAAGAAGAAAAAGAACUUCUUGAAUCACUACCCCUUAGCAAGCUGUGUAAUGAAGAACAGGAAUUGCUGCGUUUUCUAUUUGAGAACAAAUUGAAAAAAUAUAAUAAGCCUAGUGAAACGGUCAUCCCUGAAUCUGUAGAUGGCUUGCAAGAGAAUCUGGAUGUGGUAGUGUCUUUAGCUGAGAGACAUUAUUAUAACUGUGAUUUUAAAAUGUGCUACAAGCUUACUUCUGUAGUAAUGGAGAAAGAUCCUUUCCAUGCAAGUUGUUUACCUGUACAUAUAGGGACGCUUGUAGAGCUGAAUAAAGCCAAUGAACUUUUCUAUCUUUCUCAUAAACUGGUGGAUUUAUAUCCUAGUAAUCCUGUGUCUUGGUUUGCAGUGGGAUGUUACUAUCUCAUGGUCGGUCAUAAAAAUGAACAUGCCAGAAGAUAUCUCAGCAAAGCCACAACACUUGAGAAAACCUAUGGACCUGCAUGGAUAGCCUAUGGACAUUCAUUUGCGGUGGAGAGUGAGCACGACCAAGCGAUGGCUGCUUACUUCACAGCAGCACAGCUGAUGAAAGGGUGUCAUUUGCCUAUGCUGUAUAUUGGAUUAGAAUAUGGUUUGACCAAUAACUCAAAACUAGCUGAAAGGUUCUUCAGCCAAGCUCUGAGCAUUGCACCGGAAGACCCUUUUGUUAUGCAUGAGGUCGGCGUGGUUGCAUUUCAGAAUGGAGAAUGGAAAACAGCCGAAAAAUGGUUUCUUGAUGCUUUGGAAAAAAUUAAAGCAAUUGGGAACGAGGUAACAGUUGACAAAUGGGAACCUUUGUUGAACAACUUGGGGCAUGUCUGCAGAAAACUUAAAAAGUAUGCUGAGGCCUUGGAUUACCACCGUCAGGCACUGGUGUUGAUUCCUCAGAACGCAUCCACCUACUCUGCUAUUGGAUAUAUCCACAGUCUGAUGGGCAACUUUGAAAAUGCUGUGGACUACUUCCACACAGCCCUUGGUCUUAGGCGAGAUGAUACAUUUUCUGUUACAAUGCUUGGUCAUUGCAUCGAAAUGUACAUUGGUGAUUCUGAAGCUUAUAUUGCACCUAACUGGAAAUGACUCAAACGUCCACCAGUAGGAGAGAGGAGAAAUAAAUUGUGGAGCAGACAUUAAAGACAAAUUAAAAUGUUAUGACUUUGAUGUGCAUACAAUGAAGACACUAAAAAACAUUAUUUCACCUCCGUGGGAUUUCAGGGAAUUUGAAGUAGAAAAACAGACUGCAGAAGAAACGGGGCUUACGCCAUUGGAAACCUCAAGGAAAACUCCAGAUUCCAGACCUUCCUUGGAAGAAACCUUUGAAAUUGAAAUGAAUGAAAGUGACAUGAUGUUAGAGACAUCUAUGUCAGACCACAGCACGUGACUCCAGUCAGUGGUCCUGGUCCCACUGUCCCAGUGUAGGUUAGUAUUCCUUCACAUCCUCUCCAUGGCUUAAGAAUGUCCCACUUCCUAACGUGACUCCAAACUGCAUCUCUACAUUUAGGAACAGAGACCCGCCUUAAGAGACUGGAUCGCACACCUUUGCAACAGAUGUGUUCUGAUUCUCUGAACCUACAAAAUAGUUAUACAUAGUGGAAUAAAGAAGGUAAACCAUCUGUUAUGUCUUUUUUUUUCUUUUCCAAUAAACUUUUAUUUUGGACUAA